GGAAGCCGCCGAGUGAUUAGUGAGCGGAGAAGCUUUCUUCCGGCGGGAAGGGCCCCGGAGGCGGGCACUUGGGGGGAAAGUUGAGACGUGAUUACCGGGUUGGGCGGGCCCCAUCUGGGAGGGGUUUGUGGGUGAACUCGGGGUCCACCGCCCGCUGAGGAGAUGGAUGAGGACGGGCUUCCUCUCAUGGGGUCAGGCAUAGACCUGACCAAGGUGCCAGCUAUUCAACAGAAAAGAACGGUGGCUUUUCUAAACCAAUUUGUGGUGCACACUGUACAGUUCCUCAACCGCUUUUCUACAGUUUGUGAGGAGAAACUGGCAGACCUUUCACUUCGUAUCCAACAAAUUGAAACAACUCUCAAUAUUUUAGAUGCAAAGUUGUCAUCUAUCCCAGGCCUAGAUGAUGUCACAGUUGAAGUAUCUCCUUUAAAUGUCACCAGUGUCACAAAUGGAGCACAUCCUGAAGCCACUUCAGAGCAACCACAGAACAGUACACAAGACUCUGGACUACAGGAAAGUGAAGUAUCAGCAGAAAAUAUCUUAACUGUAGCCAAGGAUCCAAGAUAUGCCAGAUAUCUCAAAAUGGUUCAAGUGGGUGUACCAGUGAUGGCAAUAAGAAACAAAAUGAUAUCAGAAGGACUAGACCCAGAUCUUCUUGAGAGGCCAGAUGCUCCAGUGCCUGAUGGCGAAAGUGAGAAAACUGUAGAAGAAAGUUCAGAUAGCGAAUCUUCUUUUAGUGAUUAAGCUUAAUUUUGAUAAGAAUUACAUAUGCAUGCAUAGGGGUACAUUUACAUUCUGUAAGAGAUUGAGCCUGAACUCUCUUAGUCAUAAAAACAUCAAAUGGCCACAUGUCCACUACCAAGCUUCUUCUAUGUUAAAAAAAUAAUAAUAAAGCAGUUUUAACCUGCCAGUAUGUCUUGUUGCUAAAAUAAAGGGCCUCAAAAUGAAAAAUAGGAUAACCUAAAUAAAGUACAAUUAGUGCUACAAAUACUAAGAUAGAAUAUUUUAGAGA